GCGACCGAAACCUUCUCCCUAGCCGUUGGCACGUUCUGCUCCCGGGAACCCGUGCAGUCUAACAACCUGCAUUUAUUUCUUGACUUCUGUGUGUACAUCCCUCUGUCCUGGGGUUUCUGUCCUCUUCAGCCUAUUUUAGCGUUUCGGGGAGCUCCCCUGACUUCACAGGUGCCCCGCGCUCUGAAGGCUUCAUUGCUACCCUCCGCCAGUUGGGCGCCUUCUCCGUUCUGCUGUUGUCAAAGCAAUCUCGGCCCCAGGUUCAGUUAACUUACUGUAUGUCUCAUGUGCUGGGAGCUCUAGAGUUUGCGACGAACGAUUGACACGACCUAAUCCAUUGCUACUAGUGAAAUGACCAAAUUUUUAGAUUGAUUUGGCAGACCUGGAAAGUGAAUGGGGGCGUGGUCACCGUACCUAGCAUUUGCAAAGCUCUGCGCGAGAAGUGGAGGGAUGUGGAGAGUUAAGGCCGAGCUCCCAUUCCCGAGUCGCUGCUAGUUAGCUACAGAUAAGGCGUUGUCCUGCAUCCUCAGACUUCUUGGGAAACAAUCCUAAAGUAUUUCCCUGUCUUUUAUGUUGUUGACAGUUUUGAAAAAUACAGACCUUACAUUCUGUAGGUUGACUGCCAGCAUAUGUGCUUUCAAACCACCAGACCAAGGUUAAGCAUUCUUGGCAGGAAUACCACAGAAAUGAUGCCAUGGCUUUCUCAGUAAGUCACAUGAGGAGGCACACAGAUGUCAACCCAUCCCAACACUGGUGAUGCUAAUCUUGAUCACCUGGUUACGUUAUUAUCUGCCUGGUCUCUCCGUUUAAAAUUCGUCAUUUUUCCCUUAGUAAUUGUUGGGAAGUAAUAAUACCAGUAUCCUUUUUUCUGGGCAAACCUUAAUCCUCCAUGGCUUUAGCAUUCAUUGAUGUUUUCCACAUGAAUCGAUACCUCUAUGACGUUGCCAGAUCCUGUUUCUUUAUAUCCGCUAUUCCUUCUGCAUUUGUUAGUUGGCAUUCUACUGUAAGGAGGUGCUUUCUAUUUUAUUCAGCUGGUUGUGGUGACUCAUGCCCAUAAUCCCAACACUUUGCGAGGCUGAGGCAGGACGAGUGCUUGAGGCCAGUUCAAGCUGGGAGCCAGGCUUGGUGUCUCACACCUGCAAUCCCAGCACUUUGGAUGUUUUAGAAGAAUGUAUGUCUCUUCCCAAGCUAUCUUCUUAUUCUGGAUGGGUGGUAGAGCACGUCCUACCCCAUAUGCAGGAGAACCAACCUCUGUCUGAGACUUCGCCAUCCUCUACGUCAGCUUCAGCCCUAGAUCAACCCUCAUUUGUUCCCAAAUCUCCUGACGCAAGCUCUGCCUUUUCCCCAGCCUCCCCUGCAACACCAAAUGGAACCAAGGGCAAAGAUGAGUCCCAGCACACAGAAUCUAUGGUACUUCAGUCCUCACGGGGGAUCAAAGUGGAAGGCUGCGUCCGAAUGUACGAACUGGUACACAGAAUGAAAGGAACAGAGGGCCUGAGGCUAUGGCAGGAGGAGCAGGAGAGGAAGGUGCAAGCCCUCUCGGAGAUGGCAUCUGAACAACUGAAGCGGUUUGAUGAAUGGAAGGAACUGAAGCAGCAUAAAGAAUUCCAGGACUUGCGGGAAGUAAUGGAGAAGAGCUCCAGAGAAGCCUUGGGACACCAAGAGAAGCUAAAAGCUGAGCACCGUCACAGAGCAAAGAUUCUCAACCUGAAGCUGCGGGAAGCAGAGCAGCAGCGCGUGAAGCAAGCAGAACAGGAGCGGCUUCGGAAGGAAGAAGGCCAGAUCCGCCUGCGGGCCCUCUAUGCUCUGCAGGAGGAGAUGCUGCAGCUCAGCCAGCAGCUGGAUGCCUCUGAGCAGCACAAAGCCCUGCUUAAGGUCGACCUGGCUGCCUUCCAGACCCGAGGCAACCAGCUGUGCAGCCUCAUCUCAGGGAUCAUCCGGGCCUCUUCAGAGAGCAGCUAUCCCACAGCAGAGAGUCAAGCUGAGGCUGAGCGAGCUCUGCGGGAAAUGCGGGACCUCCUGAUGAACUUGGGGCAGGAGAUCACCAGAGCCUGCGAAGACAAGAGGAGGCAGGAUGAAGAAGAGGCCCAGGUAAAGCUGCAAGAGGCACAGAUGCAGCAGGGACCAGAGGCCCACAAAGAGCCCCCAGCUCCCAGCCAGGGCCCAGGAGGGAAACAGAAUGAAGACCUCCAGGUGAAGGUACAAGACAUUACAAUGCAGUGGUACCAGCAGCUGCAGGAUGCUUCCAUGCAGUGUGUGUUGACCUUUGAGGGCCUGACCAACAGCAAGGACAGUCAGGCCAAAAAGAUAAAGAUGGACCUCCAGAAGGCUGCUACCAUCCCAGUGAGCCAAAUCUCUACCAUUGCAGGCUCAAAACUGAAGGAGAUCUUUGACAAGAUCCACAGCCUGCUCUCUGGAAAACCUGUUCAAUCUGGUGGGCGCUCUGUGUCUGUCACACUUAACCCACAGGGGCUGGACUUUGUUCAAUACAAACUGGCAGAGAAAUUUGUGAAACAAGGCGAGGAGGAAGUGGCCUCUCACCAUGAAGCAGCAUUCCCCAUUGCAGUUGUGGCAUCCGGGAUCUGGGAGCUCCACCCCAGAGUGGGGGACCUCAUUCUUGCUCAUCUACAUAAGAAGUGUCCUUACUCUGUUCCUUUCUAUCCCACUUUCAAGGAGGGAAUGGCUUUGGAAGACUAUCAGAGGAUGCUUGGUUACCAAGUAAAGGAUUCCAAAGUGGAGCAGCAAGACAACUUUCUAAAACGCAUGUCAGGGAUGAUCCGUCUCUACGCUGCUAUCAUCCAGCUCCGGUGGCCAUAUGGAAACCGACAGGAGAUUCACCCUCAUGGCUUAAAUCAUGGAUGGCGCUGGUUGGCACAGAUCUUAAACAUGGAGCCCUUGUCAGAUGUGACAGCCACCCUCCUCUUUGACUUCCUGGAGGUGUGUGGGAAUGCCCUCAUGAAGCAAUACCAGGUUCAGUUCUGGAAGAUGCUAAUUCUCAUCAAAGAGGACUACUUUCCCAGAAUUGAAGCUAUCACAAGCUCAGGACAGAUGGGCUCCUUCAUACGCCUCAAGCAGUUCUUGGAGAAAUGUUUGCAACACAAGGACAUUCCUGUCCCCAAGGGCUUUCUGACUUCCUCCUUCUGGCGCUCCUGAUGUCACUCCAUCACCCACCAUCACCGCUGCUGCAAAGAGGCAAUAAUAAAGGAACUGAAGACAGCUGUAUUUGGGAGAAGUCAUGUCAGAUUCAGAAAUUUGCCAUUAUGUAUUUUUAUGUAUUUAUGCCUUGUGACUAGGAGAGGAGAUUUUCAUGGGUCACAAAAUUCUUGGAGGUCCCUUAGUAGAUUUGGUAGUUCCUUAAGAGAUCCACGUGAUAAAAUAAAUGGAGUUGGCCUUUCUUGUUUUUUGCAAAAGUGAUAAAAGGUCUUUAGCACUUGGUCUCCUCCCUUGUCUCUAGUGUCUUUCAGAAAGUUGGCAAUACCUUAACAAAUGCACUCUGAGCUGGAGGGAGCCCACCAUUUGCACCCACCUACCCACCCUCACCCCUGUUCAGAUGAAUUUCCAGAAAGAGCUAAGGCUCAUAAGGUUCCCUUUUAAGUAUUAUUUAAUAGUUGAGGCCAGAUACUUACAUGCAAGUCUGGGUUAUGGUUGUUUUGCCUUUCUCAGCUUGUGAAGUCAUUCUAAAGCUAGAGGAAGUAUGUGAUAUACACAUGGACUAAGGCUCAGGUGACACUAUGGCUAGAUUAACAUCUGGGAUUAGGACUGGAAACACAUGUCAUUUUGAACUAAGGGAAACUCUUUGUCAUCCUAAUUUGGAAUUUGGUCCCUGGAUGGCUAGGGAUCCAUGAACCAGGCAGGUACCUUUUUUGUUUUUGUUUUGUUUUGUUUCUUUUCUGUUUGAAUUAAGAUGGGCUAAGAUGGGGCUUGCAACAUUAAACAUGAGCUGAGCAUCCAUAAGCAUUGAAUUGGGAUUAAAUAAAGAUGUUGGGCAGGAACUGAACACUGCUAAUAUGAUGAUAAAUAUGCCUGACUAAAGCCACUACAGAAAUCCAGAGAUUGGCUGUUAAAAUUUGUUUUGUGGAAAGACUAAUUCUCUUUGAUACUGCAGAGGCAGUGGCCAUGGAUCUGUUCCUCUGUGCUAAAUGUCUUGUGGCAGGGUGUGUUUGUGGGGGAGUGUUCACUGGUACUCUUGAGUGGCCUGAAGUGACCCAUUCUAUGAAUUGUUAAUUAAGGUGCCAAAAAAAAUUAAUAAUAAAGCUUGGUUUUUUGAAAAA